AAUGCUUACCAGUGAAGCUUUUCCAGGACAGGACGAAGUUUUUGGCUGUGGGCUCUCUGGGACAGAGUGGAGCGCCUGUGGAUUUAGCCGGGGACACACCAUCCUGCUCGCAGGUGCCUGGACAGGACAGGGGACGAGGGAGGAACACUCUCUGAGGAAGCCCAACUCCUAUGAGCUCCUCUCUGGCAGGUGAGAGAAUGGUUUUGGUAUUUUUUAAAAAAAUAAAAUGAGAUAAAACAAGAGAAGGAACAGAGGCUACCGCUAGGACAGGUAGGAAAGGAGAUUACCACCCAUCCAUUCACUGAGGAGGAGCCCCCAAGAGAAACAGCAGCCCUGGAUUCCACCCGAGGGAUCCUGUCUGGUCUCGGCUUCAGCACUGCCCCUCCUGGCACUCAGUUUCACCAUCUGGGAAUCAGGAUAAGGACUCCUUCCAGGCGCUCUUCCAUUAUGGCUGUGGGCACUCAAACCAGUGAAGCUUGGGAAAGUCAUUGACCUCCAGUCGUUCUGCUGAGAAACAUCUGGCUCUAUUUCCAUGGAGACCAGGGAAUCUGAAGAUUUGGAAAAGACCCGGAGGAAAUCAGCAAGUGAUCAAUGGAACACUGAUAAUGAACCAGCCAAGGUGAAACCUGAGUUACUCCCAGAAAAAGAGGAGACUUCUCAAGCUGACCAGGAUAUCCAAGACAAAGAGCCUCAUUGCCACAUCCCAAUUAAGAGAAAUUCCAUCUUCAAUCGCUCCAUAAGACGCAAAAGCAAAGCCAAGGCCAGAGACAACCCCGAACGGAACGCCAGCUGCCUGGCAGAUUCACAGGACAAUGGAAAAUCUGUAAAUGAGCCCCUGACCUUGAAUAUCCCCUGGAGCAGAAUGCCUCCUUGCAGAACAGCAAUGCAGACAGACCCAGGAGCCCAGGAAAUGAGUGAGUCGUCCUCCACCCCGGGAAAUGGGGCCACGCCCGAGGAGUGGCCGGCCCUGGCCGACAGCCCCACCACGCUCACCGAGGCCCUGCGGAUGAUCCACCCCAUUCCCGCCGACUCCUGGAGAAACCUCAUUGAACAAAUAGGGCUCCUGUAUCAGGAAUACCGAGAUAAAUCGACUCUCCAAGAAAUCGAAACCAGGAGGCAACAGGAUGCAGAAAUAGAAGACAAUACCAAUGGGUCCCCGGCCAGUGAGGACACCCCGGAGGAGGAAGAAGAAGAGGAGGAGGAGGAGGAGCCGGCCAGCCCACCAGAGAGGAAGACUCUGCCCCAGAUCUGCCUGCUCAGUAACCCCCACUCAAGGUUCAACCUCUGGCAGGAUCUUCCCGAGAUCCGGAGCAGCGGGGUGCUUGAGAUCCUACAGCCCGAGGAGAUUAAGCUGCAGGAGGCCAUGUUCGAGCUGGUCACUUCCGAGGCGUCCUACUACAAGAGUCUGAACCUGCUCGUGUCCCACUUCAUGGAGAACGAGCGGAUAAGGAAGAUCCUGCACCCGUCCGAGGCGCACAUCCUCUUCUCCAACGUCCUGGACGUGCUGGCUGUCAGUGAGCGGUUCCUCCUGGAGCUGGAGCACCGGAUGGAGGAGAACAUCGUCAUCUCUGACGUGUGUGACAUUGUGUACCGUUAUGCGGCCGACCACUUCUCUGUCUACAUCACCUACGUCAGCAAUCAGACCUACCAGGAGCGGACCUAUAAGCAGCUGCUCCAGGAGAAGGCAGCUUUCCGGGAGCUGAUCGCGCAGCUAGAGCUCGACCCCAAGUGCAGGGGGCUGCCCUUCUCCUCCUUCCUCAUCCUGCCUUUCCAGAGGAUCACACGCCUCAAGCUGUUGGUCCAGAACAUCCUGAAGAGGGUAGAAGAGAGGUCUGAGCGGGAGUGCACUGCUUUGGAUGCUCACAAGGAGCUGGAAAUGGUGGUGAAGGCAUGCAACGAGGGCGUCAGGAAAAUGAGCCGCACGGAACAGAUGAUCAGCAUUCAGAAGAAGAUGGAGUUCAAGAUCAAGUCGGUGCCCAUCAUCUCCCACUCCCGCUGGCUGCUGAAGCAGGGUGAGCUGCAGCAGAUGUCAGGCCCCAAGACCUCCCGGACCCUGAGGACCAAGAAGCUCUUCCACGAAAUUUACCUCUUCCUGUUCAACGACCUGCUGGUGAUCUGCCGGCAGAUUCCAGGAGACAAGUACCAGGUAUUUGACUCAGCUCCGCGGGGACUGCUGCGUGUGGAGGAGCUGGAGGACCAGGGCCAGACGCUGGCCAACGUGUUCAUCCUGCGGCUGCUGGAGAACGCAGAUGACCGGGAGGCCACCUACAUGCUAAAGGCGUCCUCUCAGAGUGAGAUGAAGCGUUGGAUGACCUCACUGGCCCCCAACAGGAGGACCAAGUUUGUUUCGUUCACAUCCCGGCUGCUGGACUGCCCCCAGGUCCAGUGCGUGCACCCAUACGUGGCUCAGCAGCCAGACGAGCUGACGCUGGAGCUCGCCGACAUCCUCAACAUCCUGGACAAGACUGACGACGGGUGGAUCUUUGGCGAGCGUCUGCACGACCAGGAGAGAGGCUGGUUCCCCAGCUCCAUGACUGAGGAGAUCUUGAAUCCCAAGAUCCGGUCCCAGAACCUCAAGGAAUGUUUCCGUGUCCACAAGAUGGAUGACCCUCAGCGCAGCCAGAACAAGGACCGCAGGAAGCUGGGCAGCCGGAAUCGGCAAUGACCCCCACCCAGGGGGCCAGCGGGAGCAGGGCCUGCAUGAGACCCCGACAGAAGGUGGGGGGGGGGGGGCUCUGGGAAGCACAGGCCAGCACCUCCCCAGGUGGCAGGAUCUGGCUUGGGGUGCCCGGCCCUCAUCCCUGCCCACGCAGUGAGUGCUCAUGUGUCUUGGCCCCUUGCUCGCAAACUGGAUAAAGGGUGCCCAAGCCUCUCCUGAUGCAUUUGUAAACAAGAAGGUUUCAGCAGUAUUACACCACCUCCCUCAUGCCUCCGAGGGGGUGGAAGGGGGUGGGCACACUCCAGGGCCCCCCAUGCCCCUGGCCCCCAGGGACUGGAAGAGGCUCCCAACCCAGAGUGUCCCUGUGGGAGGCAGGCAGAAGGUGACAAUUGACACGAUUUCCUGCACGCGUCCUCCUCUACCUUGGAAGCAGUUAGAAUCUACCAGGCACAGAUGAGGCCGCCCUUGCCUGACGGAGCUUGAUGAGCAGCCCUUGGUCUCCGGUUCCAGGACUGAGAGCCCAGCUGCCUCUGCCCACCCUUCCCCAGGCCUCUGCCAGCCUCUGGCUGCACGGUCAGGCCCUGCCCCAUGGCAGGCCUGCCAGAGCUUGGCUGGGGACCCCUCCCGCCUCUGGCUCCCUGAUGGGCUGGAUGUAACUUGUGUCUUCUAGCCCCUUAAGGAGCCCAGGUGUUUUAAGGAAUGAAUUGGUCACUGCAUCUUGUAUCGAUUAUGGUUCUGAGAAAAGCAAAUAUCACUUUUGGCUGCAUUAAAAGAAGCAUCAUAUAUAAAAUAAA